ACACAAUUACCUGCCUAUGAUUUCUGUCCUAUUUAAGAUGGGUUCUAUUAUGUUUUUAUCUAUACUUGUCUUCAUUAACUUUUCGUGAUAUCAUAAGCCCCCCGAAUCCCUCGAAAGUAGAUGGGAUUCUGAGCACACACACACACAAAUUCAGAUCCCCAAAGGACAGUAAAACGAAUUAUUGGCUUAAUAUAUCAUCUUAGCUAACCAAAAGCCUGUGUCAGCUGCCAUGUUGAAAAUCUGCUUACCAGCUGCAGGGAGCUUACAAUCUGUUCUAAGGACAUAUGGAAUUGGCUAUGGAUAAUUCAUAUGCUUUCAAUCAACGAAGCACAUGUAAUGGAAUUCCAUCUGAGAAGAAAAACAACUUCCUUGUAUCAGAAGAUCAUGGACAAAAAAUCUUAAGUGUACUACAGAAUUUUAGAGAACAAAAUGUCUUUUAUGAUUUCAAAAUAAUUAUGAAAGAUGAAAUAAUCCCGUGUCAUCGUUGUGUGUUAGCAGCAUGCAGUGACUUUUUCAGGGCUAUGUUUGAAGUAAACAUGAAAGAAAGAGAUGAUGGAAGUGUUACCAUUACUAAUUUGUCCUCCAAGGCAGUAAAAGCAUUUCUCGAUUAUGCCUAUACUGGAAAAACAAAAAUAACAGAUGAUAAUGUGGAAAUGUUCUUCCAGUUGUCAUCAUUUCUUCAAGUUUCCUUCCUAUCCAAAGCUUGCAGUGACUUUUUAAUAAAAAGUAUUAAUCUUGUCAAUUGUUUACAGUUAUUAUCUAUAUCAGAUAGCUAUGGCUCCACCAGUUUGUUUGAUCAUGCAUUACACUUUGUACAACAUCACUUUUCUUUAUUAUUUAAAUCCAGUGAUUUCUUAGAGAUGAAUUUUGGAGUACUACAGAAAUGUCUGGAAUCAGAUGAAUUAAAUGUUCCUGAAGAAGAAAUGGUACUGAAAGUUGUCCUUAGUUGGACUAAACAUAACUUAGAAUCAAGGCAAAAGUAUCUGCCUCAUUUGAUUGAAAAAGUGAGAUUACAUCAGUUAUCUGAGGAGACACUUCAGGACUGUCUGUUCAAUGAAGAGAGUUUACUCAAAAGCACAAACUGUUUUGACAUAAUCAUGGAUGCAAUUAAGUGUGUGCAAGGUUCUGGUGGACUCUUCCCUGAUGCUCGACCAUCCACAACUGAGAAAUACAUAUUCAUUCACAAAACUGAGGAAAAUGGAGAAAAUCAAUAUACAUUUUGCUAUAACAUUAAAUCUGAUUCAUGGAAAAUACUGCCGCAAUCACACCUGAUUGAUUUGCCAGGAUCUAGUCUUUCGAGUUACGGAGAGAAAAUAUUCUUGACAGGUGGUUGCAAAGGGAAAUGUUGUCGAACGGUUCGACUGCAUAUUGCCGAGUCAUAUCAUGAUGCCACUGAUCAAACCUGGUGCUACUGUCCAGUGAAAAAUGAUUUCUUCUUGGUAUCAACUAUGAAAACACCAAGAACCAUGCAUACAUCAGUUAUGGCUCUCGAUAGAUUAUUUGUCAUAGGUGGAAAAACUAGAGGAUCCCGGGACAUUAAAAGUCUCUUAGAUGUUGAAUCUUACAAUCCUCUUUCCAAAGAAUGGAUAUCUGUUAGCCCAUUACCCAGAGGCAUAUACUAUCCAGAAGCAAGCACAUGCCAAAAUGUAAUUUAUGUUCUUGGAUCAGAGGUAGAGAUUACAGAUGCUUUUAACCCAUCACUUGAUUGCUUUUUUAAAUACAAUGCUACAACUGAUCAGUGGUCUGAACUAGUAGCAGAGUUUGGGCAAUUUUUUCAUGCAACAUUAAUUAAAGCUGUACCAGUAAACUGUACACUGUAUAUAUGUGACCUUUCCACCUAUAAGGUUUAUAGUUUUUGUCCAGACACUUGUGUUUGGAAAGGCGAAGGAUCUUUUGAGUGUGCAGGCUUUAAUGCAGGUGCAAUUGGAAUUGAAGAUAAAAUUUAUAUAUUAGGUGGUGAUUAUGCACCAGAUGAAAUCACAGAUGAAGUGCAGGUCUACCACAGCAACAGGUCUGAAUGGGAAGAAGUUUCACCAAUGCCUAGAGCCUUAACAGAAUUUUACUGCCAGGUGAUUCAGUUUAAUAAAUACAGAGACCCAUGGUUUUCUAAUCUAUGUGCUUGAACAUUCUAAAACGAGUCCAGUUCUAGUAACCUAAAGUAAAUUUGUUAACCAAAAUGAUAGGUAAAAAGAUCUAUACAUCUUAAUGAAAUAAAACAUUCCUGCUUUUAGUUAUUAUGUAUGUACACCAUAUAUGAAUAAACAGUUUCCAAAAACUUAAAAUACAAAAUAUAUUUUACCAAAAAUUAUACUGAAUAUAAUUUAACCUUGGGGAAUCCAGAAUACUUAGUAUUUUCACAUGAAACUACAAAUCAUAGACUCUGACACUUUGAUUUUUAAAGUACUCUGUCCAUAAAAGAUUUGUACUGUUUAGAUGGGAGAAACCUCUAGAGAGAGUAAAAAUGAAUUACACUGUAUCUUAUAUGAAGUAAAAAAUAAAUCAGAGGUGAGAAUAUUGUUACUGCGGGUAUGAGUUGUUGAAUUCCUAUCAUUUGUGAUGAUUGGUUAACUUCUUUUAGGUACCCUUUUUACCCUUUUUUAGUUCAGAAAUAAUUCUCCCAGCUUUAUAAAUAGUACACUAAACAUAGUUUAACUUUUUUUAAUGACUCAUUUUUUCAUUAAAAGCAUAAUGUACCAUGUUAUAAUGCCAUUAGCAGUUACUUAAAUGCUUUAAAAAUUGCUGAUUAGUUUUCAAUGUCAGUUGGUUUCAAUUUCUAGCUCUCUCUCUCUCUCUCCUCCCCCCCUCUCAUUUUCUGGUUCAAUCUUAGUAAAUUAACAUUCUGGAUUUAAUUAGUAGUUCUAAGUUACACCUGGCCUGAGUUUAUGUUAACAUGUAACCCUCAAUUGGAAAUUUUUGGAUUCUGGGAUGGCAGUACUAAAAUACUUUUUAUGUAUCAUUGCUAGGUUCCAGCCUAAUUAAGGACAUAGAAAAUUGACCUCUAAUUAAGUGGAUCAUUAUUAUGGCAUUUCUUAAGCUUUAUCCAAAUUUCAGCUACAUAAAACAUUUCAGGAUUUAAAUUAGUACCAUAUCAAUUUUCUGUGAUGAUGUAUACCAACUAUAAAGCACUAUGUUGGUUUACUACUUCAGUAAAUUAUUCUUAGUGAAUUAUUUUCUAAAUUAAAAAAAAUGACUUGGCUUUUGGUAUUGAUAAUAGUAUUCACAACCUGCAUCUGUUAAGAUGUUUGAUCUUUAACCCACACAAUGUAAGGGUACUGUUGUCAUUGUUCUCAGGUAGGUGAUUCUGCCUUCCAAGAGUAUAUGUUUCUUUAAUCAGUUUAAAAGAUAAAGGCAUUUUGGGUUUUAAGACCCCUGCUUUACAUCUCAGGUAAUGUGUAGAUUGUACUUCUCUGGAACCAAAUGUAGUUUUCUACACUCAGUUGUAAAUGUUAAUCUUUCUCAAAUGUGCACAUUCUUUAAAAGUGUGUUCCUAAGUAGAAAUACACCUAAAUGAAGAUUCUCUUAUUUUAUCAUAUAAAUUUAUGCAACGAUAAGUUCCAAAUGUAUUUUUCAAAACAGAAUGGAAUAUCAGAGUACAUUUUCAUGAAGUUUAAAAAUCAAGGACUGUUCCUGAUUAGAUGACGUAUUUAUUGGUGGCCUUCUUAUCUAAGCACAUGAGUAGUUGGCUCUGAACUUUGUGUAUUUGAAAAAGGAAAAUUCAGUGGAGGCUUUUGUUUGUGUGUGUGUGGCUUUGAAAACAAAUUAUUUGAGAAAGACCAUAACACAGUGAGUAGCCUAUAUGUGCAUUUACUGAAUUGUUAAUUUAAGGAUAUAUAUUAAUAGAGUAUGUUUAAAAUAAAUAUUGUUUUCAUCACUGA